GCUCGACCCCUCCCCCCGUGGCUCGGCCGCCCCCUCCCCCCGCUCCGCCCGCUCAGAGCAUAAUGGCAGCGUCUGAGGUUGCUGGUGUUGUGGCCAAUGCCCCCAGUCCUCCGGAAUCUUCUAGUUUAUGUGCUUCCAAAUCAGACGAAGGUCUCCCAGAUGGUCUAAGCACCAAAGACUCUGCACAGAAGCAGAAGAACUCGCCUCUGUUGAGUGUAAGUAGCCAAACAAUAACCAAGGAGAAUAACAGAAAUGUCCAUUUGGAGCACUCAGAGCAGAAUCCUGGUUCAUCAGCAGGUGACACCUCAGCAGCGCACCAGGUGGUUUUAGGAGAAAACUUGAUAGCCACAGCCCUUUGUCUUUCUGGCAGUGGGUCUCAGUCUGAUUUGAAGGAUGUGGCCAGCACAGCAGGAGAGGAGGGGGACACAAGCCUUCGGGAGAGCCUCCAUCCAGUCACUCGGUCUCUUAAGGCAGGGUGCCAUACUAAGCAGCUUGCCUCCAGGAAUUGCUCUGAAGAGAAAUCCCCACAAACCUCCAUCCUAAAGGAAGGUAACAGGGACACAAGCUUGGAUUUCCGACCUGUAGUGUCUCCAGCAAAUGGGGUUGAAGGAGUCCGAGUGGAUCAGGAUGAUGAUCAAGAUAGCUCUUCCCUGAAGCUUUCUCAGAACAUUGCUGUACAGACUGACUUUAAGACAGCUGAUUCAGAGGUAAACACAGAUCAAGAUAUUGAAAAGAAUUUGGAUAAAAUGAUGACAGAGAGAACCCUGUUGAAAGAGCGUUACCAGGAGGUCCUGGACAAACAGAGGCAAGUGGAGAAUCAGCUCCAAGUGCAAUUAAAGCAGCUUCAGCAAAGGAGAGAAGAGGAAAUGAAGAAUCACCAGGAGAUAUUAAAGGCUAUUCAGGAUGUGACAAUAAAGCGGGAAGAAACAAAGAAGAAGAUAGAGAAAGAGAAGAAGGAGUUUUUGCAGAAGGAGCAGGAUCUGAAAGCUGAAAUUGAGAAGCUUUGUGAGAAGGGCAGAAGAGAGGUGUGGGAAAUGGAACUGGAUAGACUCAAGAAUCAGGAUGGCGAAAUAAAUAGGAACAUUAUGGAAGAGACUGAACGGGCCUGGAAGGCAGAGAUCUUAUCACUAGAGAGCCGGAAAGAGUUACUGGUACUGAAACUAGAAGAAGCAGAAAAAGAGGCAGAAUUGCACCUUACUUACCUCAAGUCAACUCCCCCAACACUGGAGACAGUUCGUUCCAAACAGGAGUGGGAGACGAGACUGAAUGGAGUUCGGAUAAUGAAAAAGAAUGUUCGUGACCAAUUUAAUAGUCAUAUCCAGUUAGUGAGGAACGGAGCCAAGCUGAGCAGCCUUCCUCAAAUCCCUACUCCCACUUUACCUCCACCCCCAUCAGAGACAGACUUCAUGCUUCAGGUGUUUCAACCCAGUCCCUCUCUGGCUCCUCGGAUGCCCUUCUCCAUUGGGCAGGUCACAAUGCCCAUGGUUAUGCCCAGUGCAGAUCCCCGCUCCUUGUCUUUCCCAAUCCUGAACCCUGCCCUUUCCCAGCCCAGCCAGCCUUCCUCACCCCUUCCUGGCUCCCAUGGCAGAAAUAGCCCUGGCUUGGGUUCCCUUGUCAGCCCCCACGGUCCACACAUGCCCCCUGCCGCCUCCAUCCCACCUCCCCCAGGCUUGGGCGGUGUUAAGGCUUCUGCUGAAACUCCCCGGCCCCAACCAGUAGACAAACUGGAGAAGAUCCUGGAGAAGCUGCUGACCCGGUUCCCACAGUGCAAUAAGGCCCAGAUGACCAACAUUCUUCAGCAGAUCAAGACAGCACGUACCACCAUGGCAGGCCUGACCAUGGAGGAACUUAUCCAGUUGGUUGCUGCACGACUGGCAGAACAUGAGCGGGUGGCAGCAAGUACUCAGCCACUUGGUCGCAUCCGGGCCUUGUUCCCUGCUCCACUGGCCCAAAUCAGUACCCCAAUGUUCUUGCCUUCUGCCCAAGUUUCAUAUCCUGGAAGGUCUUCACAUGCUCCAGCCACCUGUAAGCUAUGUCUAAUGUGCCAGAAACUCGUCCAGCCCAGUGAGCUGCAUCCAAUGGCGUGUACCCAUGUAUUGCACAAGGAGUGUAUCAAAUUCUGGGCCCAGACCAACACAAAUGACACUUGUCCCUUUUGUCCAACUCUUAAAUGACGGACCUGACUGGGGAGGAAGAAGAAGAGAAACUGAUGUGAACAGGAAGCGCGGGUUCAAGAUUUCUAAAACUCUAUAUUUAUACAGUGACAUAUACUCAUGCCAUGUACAUUUUUAUUAUAUAGGUAAUGUGUGUAUAGAAAGUCUGUAUUCCAAUGUUCGUAAAUGAAACUAUGUAUAUUAUGCAGAAACAGUCUGUUCCCCCUCAUCUUGCAAUUCCUUUGGGGGAUGCAGAUUGUAGGGAAGAUGAUGUUUAGUUUGGCCUUGAAAUUAUGAUAUCCCUGCCCAGGGCUGUUUUCAAAUACAAUAUAAAAACCACCUAGGAACCUGCUGUUGCUCUAAGGCCAUUCUGCUUUGGUUUGGCUCAGCCUCUAGUCCAUUUCCUUAAGGCUCAUGUAUGCAGAUUUAAAGCCUGGUGCUCACCCACUGUCCAACCAGAUGCCUUGCUUACCGAAAGCCUCCAGAAGCCUCAGUAUUGUUUUAGCCACUCUACUCCAAAUGGAUAAAAUGAGACUCUGAUUGAGGAAAAAAAAGUAACCCUAGUAGUUUGACUUCUUAUUGAAUAUUUUACUGUGUUAACGCUCAUUAUUUAUACAGACAUUAGGUUUACAGAAUAUUCUGUUUUACAUCACCAAAAUUCACAGUCCGAGAAUAACAACAUAACCAGGUCCCAAUUCCUCCAUGUACCCCACAAGCUUCUGUCCACCCUAUUUUCUGGACAGAAAUUAGCACAACCCACAGGUUUUUCCUGGGCCAAGUCUUCCUUUGCUGCCACUGUCUUGGCUUCUAAUCAAGCUCUGACAGGCCAACAUUGUGAAGUCCUCACCCUUUCCCAUUCACUUCUGGUCUCCUAGUCUAGCUAAUCCCCCUCCCCCAGAAGGUUAAGGCAGUUGGUUCACAACCAAGUUGUUUGGUGACCUUGGGUGAGCUCCAGACAGGCACUGGGGUGAGGAGAUGUCUGUGCAAAAUUACUUGUAGAAUGAUCUUGGGAUGCUGGAUUUUAAUUUUUGAAGCAAGAAAGUUAGGGGGGGACAUAUUUCCUGUCCUGGGAAAAAUGGAGACCAAAGUGAUAUUAAGAAAGUAGUUUGGAUUUCAAAUUUAUAAAUCACUUGCUCUGUGGGUAGCUAUCAGGAACUAGAUCAUUUUCCACCUCUGCUUAUUGUACUUCUUAAUUUUAGGUUUUAUACCUGGGAAAGCUGUGACUCUAUUAGAGCUUUGAAUCUUUUCCUAUCCUUUUAUCUUUACUCCUACAGGGAAUGGCCUCAGCUCCCUUCUCUUUUAGAAUUAAACAAGUAAAAACUAA